CAUCCAGCAGCAGAAACCUCACCCAGCAGCGUCUUUUCCGGUCUCAUUCACCAGCGCCGCCCACCGCUCAACCAAUCCCUGGCCAAAAGAAUGGGACCGCCUGGAAGGCUGGACCAAACAGGACCUGCCCUCUGGGGCUGGGGAGAGGCCCAGAUGAAGGCUGCAGGACAGGAUGGACUCCUAGACCUCUGUUACCAGCAGUGACUACCUCUGUCUGGGUGGUUGGAACAUGUUUGAAUUUUAUUCUAAGUACUGUCUACAAGUUCUGCAAUAAACCUUGACUCUUCUUUUAAUAAUGCAAAAGGAAUCGAAGUGAUUGUUUGAAAGGGAGAGGAAGAAAGAGAGAGGGAGGGAGGGAAGAAUGGAGGGAGGCAGGGAAGGAGACAGAGAGAGUAGAAUCCAGCCACCGGAAAAUCCAGAAUAGCUGGCUUUGCUUAAUCCAUGCCUGGAAAUAACUGCUGGGUUUGCAACAACUUCUCUCCCGGAGACAGACCAAGGAAACUACAAAACUGCAGGAAGGAUUGAAGGGCCGGGCACAGUGGCUCACGCCUGUAAUCCCAACACUUUGGGAGGCCGAGGUGGAUUGGAUCACCUGAGAUCAGGAGUUCGAGACCAGCCUGGCCAACAUGGUGAAACCUCGUCUCUGCUAGAAAUACAAAAAUAAGCCGGGCGUGGUGGCGUGCGCCUAUAGUCCCAGCUACUCGGGAGGCUGAGGCAAGAGAAUCGCUUGAACCUGGGAGGUGGAGGUUGCAGUGAGCUGAGAUCGUGCCACUGCACUCCAGCUUGGGCGACAGAGUGAGAAUCUGUCAGGUGGAUUCUGAGGGUACUCUGACCCCACGAACCCAGCAUGAAAUCUUCCAGGCAUUAAGGAACAUUGAGGAUGUGGAGGAUUGGAAAUCCCUCCAGGGAAAAUACACUUCUCUUGAGCAGGGUCACGAGGGGUGGGGGCAAUGUGGGAGGUGGGGCAAAUCCAAAGACAAGGUCAACAGCAAUAAUAAUAAUAACAAUGACAGGCAUUUGUUGCUUGUUGGCUGGGCCUCUUGCAUACAGUUCUCCCAACAUCCCUGUGAGGUGGUGAUGCUUAUCCCCAUUCUCCAGGGGAGGAGGCUGAGGCCCAGAGAGGUGAAGUCGUGUGCCACAAAAUACCCCAGCCAUAUGGUGGUAGAACCAAGUUUUCAGCCAGACUCACCAGCUCACAGCAGAGCUGCCCUGGACUCUACAGCCAUUCAGUGUAUAGCUGGGCCACUCCAUCAUUCAAGGCAGUUCAACGUCAAGAUUCCUGAUUUGCCUCAACCUGGGGCCUCUAGAAGAUACCAUCACCCCCAACAAGCUGAAGACGUGUGUCCGGAACACUCAGACACACACAAAGUGCUAUGGAUACACCACACCCCGACCUAGCUGUCUCUUCCUGAUGGACCUCACUGGGUAGAAAUGCCUGGCACCGCCUGCCUCAGAUCCCUAGGGAGUAUAGGUGGAGCCUCCAGAGCCCAUGGACAGGGCAUGCUGGGGCUGGGCCAGCCCCAGCGGUGUCUCUAAGGCACCCCUGGGAUCCCCACUGAGCUGGCCUACUUCAGACAGCCAGGGCCCACCCCUCUGGCCCCCUUAGUGUCCAGCUCGUGGCCCCUUGGCAUUUCCACAAGACGCCAAGAUGGAGAUUCCCAUGGGGACCCAGGGCUGCUUCUCAAAGAGCCUCCUGCUCUCAGCCUCAAUCCUGGUCCUCUGGAUGCUCCAAGGCUCCCAGGCAGCUCUCUACAUCCAGAAGAUUCCAGAGCAGCCUCAAAAGAACCAGGACCUUCUCCUGUCAGUCCAGGGUGUCCCAGACACCUUCCAGGACUUCAACUGGUACCUGGGGGAGGAGACGUACGGAGGCACGAGGCUAUUUACCUACAUCCCUGGGAUACAACGGCCUCAGAGGGAUGGCAGUGCCAUGGGACAGCGAGACAUCGUGGGCUUCCCCAAUGGUUCCAUGCUGCUGCGCCGCGCCCAGCCUACAGACAGUGGCACCUACCAAGUAGCCAUUACCAUCAACUCUGAAUGGACUAUGAAGGCCAAGACUGAGGUCCAGGUAGCUGAAAAGAAUAAGGAGCUGCCCAGUACACACCUGCCCACCAACGCUGGGAUCCUGGCGGCCACCAUCAUUGGAUCUCUUGCUGCCGGGGCCCUUCUCAUCAGCUGCAUUGCCUAUCUCCUGGUGACAAGGAACUGGAGGGGCCAGAGCCACAGACUGCCUGCUCCGAGGGGCCAGGGAUCUCUGUCCAUCUUGUGCUCGGCUGUAUCCCCAGUGCCUUCAGUGACGCCCAGCACAUGGAUGGCGACCACAGAGAAGCCAGAAUUGGGCCCUGCUCAUGAUGCUGGUGACAACAACAUCUAUGAAGUGAUGCCCUCUCCAGUCCUCCUGGUGUCCCCCAUCAGUGACACAAGGUCCAUAAACCCAGCCCGGCCCCUGCCCACACCCCCACACCUGCAGGCGGAGCCAGAGAACCACCAGUACCAGGACCUGCUAAACCCCGACCCUGCCCCCUACUGCCAGCUGGUGCCAACUUCCUGAUGGGUCCUGGGCCAGGCCAGCCAGGGAGAAGACAAGGCCCCAGCCCUCCUCUGGGAGCCUCACACCUGAGACCAGCAGGACAAGGCCAUUGGGGGCUGUGGGGCCGAUGAGGUGGACUCAGCCAAAGACUCAGCAGCACAUGGGGCAGGUGUCCUGGCAGGGGGACAGGAGACUGUAACAGGCCCAGGUCCUUGUGCAGCCCGUGAAUGCACGCCCGCCUUCGGUCUGUUCCUUCAAGCAAGCUGGCCUGGGCCAUGUGCCUGUGAAAGGCAGGCUCUGGCCCCUUUCCAUGCCAAAGUCCCCCAAGAUCUGGAUAUCUGGGGACAAGAUGGUGGCCUCAGGCCUGCCUCCCAGGCAGUUGGCUGGGCUCCCAACUGUCUGUCCUCAAUGCCCUACCCCAACUCCACUAGUGACCCUCAGAGUCUUCUCCCCUUAGGACAAGGCAGACACCCCACCAUGCGGGCCUCAGGUGGCAGAGAGGCCCAGCCUCACAGGCCUGUGGCCCCACACACCAGUCCCAGCAAGGUGACCACGGCUGCUGGACCCCUUCCCUGUUCAGGCAGGCCCAGCCCCUCUCAGAACCUGCUGCCAGCUGCUGGUCUUGGCCCCCACCCUGAAUCUUACUGAGUCCCUCUGGGCAGCAGCUCCCUUCUCCACCCCACCCCAGCACCCGUCCCAAAUGUGGCCUCAGCUUGUCCUCCCCUUCCCCAAACUAUGCAUUCAUUCAGCAAUAAAUGAGCCUUUGCUGUAUGCCAGACCCAGUUCUAGGCUCUUGCAGCCCUGGUAGAAAGCAAAACAAAAACUCCCGCUUUCCCAGAGGGUCACUUGGCAGGGGAAAGAAUCAGGAAAUAAAAUAAAUAAUGAA